CUCUCUACACAGAAUCGGCUGUUGAGUGUGCUCUCAGUGGAGCUUUGGUUUUAGCUGUUCUCUGACAAAGAGCUUGUUCUGAGCUGCACAUCUCGUCCUCUUUGUUCAGCCUCAGGCUUCAAGCAUUGAAUCCUAAAUAUUCUCCAGCUGGGAAUCAGACAAGGGCAGAAAUGAAGAACCCAGAAGCCCAGCAGGAUGUUUCAGUUUCCCAGGGAUUUCGCAUGUUGUUUUACACGAUGAAACCCAGUGAAACUUCAUUCCAAACAUUAGAAGAGGUGCCUGAUUAUGUAAAAAAGGCAACUCCAUUUUUCAUUUCUUUGAUGCUGCUUGAACUUGUUGUCAGCUGGAUUCUCAAAGGAAAGCCACCAGGUCGCCUGGAUGAUGCUUUAACGUCAAUCUCAGCUGGUGUUCUGUCUCGACUUCCAAGUCUAUUUUUCAGGAGCAUUGAACUGACCAGUUAUAUUUAUAUCUGGGAGAACUACAGGCUGUUCAAUUUGCCUUGGGAUUCUCCAUGGACUUGGUAUUCAGCCUUCUUAGGAGUUGACUUUGGCUACUACUGGUUCCAUCGUAUGGCUCAUGAAGUUAAUAUUAUGUGGGCCGGACACCAAACACAUCAUAGUUCUGAAGACUAUAACUUAUCCACAGCACUGAGACAGUCUGUCCUCCAGAUAUAUACUUCCUGGAUUUUCUACUCUCCCCUGGCCCUCUUCAUACCCCCUUCAGUAUAUGCUGUUCAUCUUCAAUUCAAUCUUCUUUACCAAUUUUGGAUCCAUACAGAGGUCAUCAAUAACCUUGGUCCUUUGGAACUGAUUCUUAAUACUCCUAGCCAUCAUAGGGUUCAUCAUGGCAGAAAUCGUUAUUGCAUAGACAAAAAUUAUGCUGGUGUUCUUAUUAUUUGGGAUAAAAUUUUUGGGACAUUUGAAGCAGAAAAUGAAAAAGUUGUAUAUGGCUUAACACAUCCCAUUAAUACAUUUGAACCAAUCAAAGUGCAGUUCCAUCACUUAUUUUCCAUAUGGACUACAUUCUGGGCCACACCUGGAUUCUUCAAUAAGUUUUCUGUCAUAUUUAAGGGACCGGGAUGGGGUCCAGGUAAACCAAGACUUGGUCUCAGUGAAGAAAUUCCAGAGGUCACCGGCAAAGAAGUUCCCUUCUCAUCAUCUUCAUCUCAGCUAUUAAAGAUAUAUACAGUUGUACAGUUUGCUCUGAUGUUGGCAUUUUAUGAAGAGACCUUUGCAGAUACAGCUGCACUGUCGCAAGUUACUCUCCUUCUGAGGGUUUGCUUCAUUAUCCUGACCUUGACUUCCAUUGGAUUUCUUCUGGAUCAAAGACCCAAGGCAGCUAUUAUGGAAACUCUCCGUUGCUUGAUGUUCUUAAUGCUGUACCGAUUUGGUCACCUGAAGCCUCUUGUCCCUUCAUUGUCAUCUGCUUUUGAGAUUGCCUGACAAGGUUGCCUUGUCCUUGCCCCUGCCUGCCCUCUGGUGGAGAAUAGCAGGAUGGUAAAAGGAAAAUAAGGAGAAAAUCCAUGGUGAGAUGAUGAAUAAGUACCUAAGAUAGGUGCUACCACAAGUUACUGGAUAAUCACUUCUAGUAACACUUUUAUUUAUAUAUUUCAAAUAUAACUAUAUAUUCUUAAUAUUAAGUUUGAUUUUAACUACUCAAUGUCAACUAGCUCAUCCUGCUUUGAGAUGGCAGGAGGGAAACCCUGGGGGAAGGGGGAAGCAAGAGAAAAUUUUUAUCCAGUGUGCUCUCCAAGAUUUAACUAAAUCAUUUGUUAUAGUUGACUUUCUUCUUAAACAUUGUGUGUAACUGAAAGAAUAAUAAUAAUGCCUCAGAUUUUCAUGAGAAUAUAUGAUGGUGGGCUUAGAGGAAGGCUUAUCAUUUUCCAGUUCUGUAUUUUUUAGUUGACAAUUUACUAGUAAUUUCAUCUCCAUUCAUGCAGACAACAUCCUAUAAAAUAAAUAUGUCGGUUUAUUUGAGUUCAUUGGACUGUUGACAAAUCAUGGCCCUAUAAAGUACGAAUCAGGGACUUUUGAAACAGAUAAACCGAACCCUUGACUCAUAACGAAACUGAAUAAAUAAGAUUUUUAUUACAAAUAACUUGACAAACCCAAAUCUUUCCACUUUAUCUUCCUUAUAUUUCUGUAAUAAAACUGAUGUAACAAACCCUAAAUCACCACCAUUUAGUAAUAGCAAAAUUGAAAACUCAAAAAUUUUCAGUUUUCUUUAUACCAACAGAUUUGAGAUUGUACCCAAAAUUUCUGUCCUGGUUUGGCCUUGAAUUUCAAUCCAAUUCUUCCCUUCCACAGCUGUUUGCUGGGUACGCUGUUAUUAAAUAAUGGGGCUCUGUGGAGAAGACCUCAAGGGAGUUGAGGGGAUCGAGAGAGCUGGAGAAGAGAAAGGGAUGAAAGAGACUUUAAAAGAUGAAACAAAUGUUAGGAGUUUAUGUAGGUCAAGACAUUUAAAGUUAACUUUCAUUUGUAUUGUAAUGGGGGAAUUUUCCAGCUAUUAAUAUUUUGAGCAGAGAGCCCACUUAUUUCAUAGAAUAAAAAAUUAAGAGGAUGCCGUCAAGCAUUGCAUAAAGGCAUUGACGUGGCAUUGUUAUAUGUAAAAGGACUGAAAAUUGAACUAACACAAGUUUGUUAUUUUAGACUUGGGCCUCUAGGAGUUCAUGGAAAAUCGUAUUGGAUAUUUUGAGCUAUUAGAGAUAUACCCACAGACCUAUUCUCUUCCAGGUCUAUAUCAUGAUUUUAACGAUAAAAGUUUAAGAGAUUAUCAGAGAAAGAAUUGAUCCUCACAAUUAAACACAGCAACAAGAAUAUAUGUGUAUGUGCUGUGUGUGGGGGUAAACAUACAAGAGUAUACAUACAUGUAUUUCCUUGUAUCUUUCUUUUCUACCAAACAUUUCUAAAGUCAGGGCUAACUUAAUAUUUCAUUUUUCCAUAGCUUGUAUCAAGUUCCCCAUGCUCCACUUCCUUCUUCUGCUUUUUAGCACCUUCAUAUUCCUCACAUUCUUUUAUGGCAGAGCACAACUCUCUCACUUUUUCUAACAAGAAACACACAUUGCAGUUAAACAGCCGAGGUCAUCCCCAUGCUCGCGUCACAGGUCAAGCAAGAUCACUUACAUUUUUUAGGGGGUCAUUUCUUCUCACUGGGUGGGAUAUGACCUUGUUCCUGUUUCCAGAAAAGAAACCACCCCAGAUGUUCACCACCCCUUCUCUCUCUUUUUUUUUUCUGUUUUUCCAUUCUCUUCCUUGUUUGAUGCCAAAUACACAAUUAGACAUUCAUCUUGCUAGUAUUUUUCUAUGUUAAAAAAGAUCUUUAUUUUUACCUAAUGUAUCUUAAAUACAAAAAUAAGCCAAAAAUACAGAAAAUCUGACAUUUAAUUAAAAUUUAGGGGAUAGAUACUAUUUUAUAAUUUGAAUGUACCAUUCUGAAAACUCCUUGGUAUUUUCAGCAUAUUAUAAAGUCACUAUUAAGAUACAUUUCUCUCUGCAUCUGUGCCGCCAUCUUAAUAUCAUCUGUGGGCUGCACUUUUUUUUCAAAACCAUCUGCAUUUUGAGCUGUCUUUUGAGAAAUGGCUGUAAGAAUACAAUUAAUUCUGUUCUCCCUGUGUGGAUUGUUCCUCCUGGGUUUUCAUUGACCAUCCCAGACAUUCAGCUUUCAAGAUCCUUUAGAUUUACUCACUGAAUACAACCAAGUUUGCAGUGGUUUUGUACUGAUUACAAAUAUAUAGAUACUUUUCCUGACUUUAUUUUUUACAAACAUAGUCAAGAUGUAAUGCCUGCAGAAAUUAUUACUCUCAGUAACAAUUUCAUGGCUUCAGUCCUAUCUUUAUGAAGCUUAACUCUAGUUGACUGCUCCAUGACUUACAUGAAUUGAACACAUACUGUAUUCCAGCAACCGUACCAUAUGAUGGAGGUACAGCAAUGAACAAAACAAAACAAAAAGGCUUCUCUUCAUGGAGUUUACAGUCUAGUGAAAAUAGACUUUUAAAUUGAAAACAGCUAAUAUAUUAGAAAAUAAAUACCUGCUUUGUAACAAGUACUGCGCUAAAAGCUCUAUGCCAGUCUCCUUGAUUUAUGUAUUUUUUAAUUGUCAUUUUCAAAGAUUUUAAUCUUUAAGGAACCUUUGCAUUUUAAUUUCUGUAUUAUAUUUUGAAGUUUGUUCUUAUUAAGUUCUAGAGUUAGAACAAAAUAAUAAAUUUUGAAAUAAAAUCUGGUGGAAAUACUGUAUACCUUUUAUUGCCAUACCAACUUUAUUAGACCCCAACUUUAUUCAUACCCUGUUAAAAGUCCAUAACCAAUAUAAUUUUUGAAGAAAGUUCAUGGUCUAAUUUUUGGUUAGAAGAAGAAUUCUGUAAAUUAAAAUCAAAUUUCUCAUGAUGUGACACAUUUUUUCCCAAAGAAUGUUUAUUUCAGAGGUAAAAAAUAUUUGAUGAAGACCAAACUAAUAGUUUAUCUUCAAGAGAAAUUAUCAAAUUUUAUCCUUAAAAAUCUAAUAAGUACCAAUUAAUUCAUUGACUCAAAAGGAUAAUUAAUGUUUUGAUUGUGAAUUAUUAUAAAACAAAAUGCUAGCAAAAACAGGCAAACUUGUAUGUACCACAAAGGGUUUUAUCAAAUCUCAUUAUACUAUAUCCACUUAACAUAUUUUAAGUAAAUAAAACAUUAAGAAAAAGUUGAGGAGCUCUCUUUACUUAUUCUCCUCUGAUACUAUUUCCCUUCUUUCAGCACCAGAAGUAACUUCAGGCAGGAUGACAUUUUGACUUUCAUGAGCCUUAGGCACUUUUGCCUUCUUGAGCCCUUCUUGAGCCCAUUUCUAUAUAAUAAAAAAUUAUUCAGCUGUUAAAAAUUUAACAGUAAAAAUAUUAUAUUAUACAACAGUGUUUCUAAAAAGAUGUAUGUAAUUCAGAUUGGUUUCACUGUUAUGUAUCCAAUAUUAUUAUAGUCAUUUUUUCUUGGGUUUUUAAAAGAAAUGAAAAUUAAAACAUUUCUAUUAUCCUCUAAAAGUAUCGUGGACCUUCAACACUGUGAAUUCAGCCUUUUAGCAUUCCUAUGCUUUUGCUUACAUAUUCAUCUGUAUAGAUUUUUAAAUUACCACUUAUUGUAUUGGUUUUAGAAAAUGUAUUGAGAACUAGUUGUAUAAUUUUAGUUGGUUUAAAAAAAAACAAGCAAACAGUAUUUGCCUUCAUUUUGAGAACAUAUUCAGCAUUUGCUUUCUUUUUUUUUUCCUGAGACUGAAGCUCUCUCUGUCUCCCAGGCUGGAGUGCAGUG